GGUCCCCCAAACGGAGGGGACGAUGCCCUUCCUCGCCGGACCCUAGGCAUUGCGGAGAGUGAGCCUCUGUGGACCGGCUUUAAGCCCCCAGGAAGGUGUUUGAGGAUGAGGACUAGCAGCACCAGCGUGGGGGCCGUUGAGGGUGUUGAGAGAUGUGAAGGUUAGUAGCAGUAUAGUAAGAAUUGUUGGAGAGGAGGUUUCCAGAUGACUGUUGGUAGGUGUUGAGUAAGGAGAAAACACUGCUUUCCUUUAAAGAUCGCACAAGCAGUCCUCUGAGGUCCAACAACAGAUUAGAGUUAUUCCCAGUUGGAGUUCUGUAGUUUACUACCGUGUGCCAGCUCAUAAAGUGCGUAAAAGCAGGAUUUGAAGGGUGAGGGACAGGUGAGGCAUAAAGUAAGCUGCAUAAAAAGAUCCAAAGUUUGUUAAUGUGUUAAAGUGUAAAUCCUUCUGUUUCUACUGAAAUGUAACUUAUUUAAAUUAUUUAAGAAAACUUGCCACCUUUGGUCCAGACCGGGCUUGUCAGUUCGAUGUGUUUCUUCAGUGACGUUUGUCAAUCAGGCAGUCAUUUUGGCAUACAGUAUAUUUACUUCUGGUUUCUAAAAGAACAAGAAUGAAUGAGAAAAGGGAACAGUUUGGCAAACUGAGCUUUCUUUGCGCACUUUUUCAUUUUGAAAGGAUAAGAGAAUUUACUUUUUUCUUUGCUUUAGUAAUGAUUUGCAGUAGUAUACAAGAACACGUGGAAGAAGAAAGGGUUUUUUGAGAUGAGAGUUUAAUUUUGCACAGUGUUAAAUUAUAAAGGGCCUCAUCACCCAUGGUAAGUUUUGUGAUGGUGUGUUUUAUGAACACCGGAAGAAUACAGGCACAUACAUAUACAUGCUUUUUAGUCAGUGUGUGAUAUGAAUCUUUACAACCGUAGGGACAGCCCCCGCCCCCACUUGCUUACAACUGGCUUAAUCAAGGGAAAGACUUCAGUGAAGGUAAAUAUUAAAUAUGUGAUUUUCAUCUUCACAUCUGAAAGAACAUAAUCUGCAUUCAGUCACCCUGAAUUUUCAUCCAUAUGUUUAUUUGAUGGAGUCUUCCCCUCAGUUAUAGAUACCACAUUGUGUACAGUUUGUUGGAGCAAACAGAGCUAACGUCGAUUAUAUUCAGGCACUGGAGAUCCUCACAGCUACCCUAUGCUAAAGAUAAUGUUAUGCCGAUUGCACAGAACAAUACUAACCUCCAAUAUUCUUUGGCGACUUCGCUGAGGAGAUUAUAUAGCUGGUAAAUUGCAGAGCUAGAACUCAAACUCAUGUAGGUCUGAUUCUAGAGUGUGUGUUCUUUCACCAUACUCUGCGUAAGUUUUUGUGCUGACUGAUACAAAUUUUAUGAAAAUGGAAAUUUGUGUUACAAAGAAACCUUUCAGUUCUGUUGGUAAUCUUGAAAGCUUUCAGUGUCCUUGGCUCCAGAUAAUCUCAAGGUUUUUUUUUCUUUUCAGAUGCGUCCAUUUUCUAGCCAGAGGUAACAUUUGAGCUAGAAGUCUGCUGAUCUGUAAAGAGAUUCCUGAUAGCUGGUAGUGACCUAUCUGAAAUUCAGAUAUUUUCAGUUACUUUGCCUCUUGUGUCAGCAUGCCCAAGAUACUUCAAAGAACAAAUAUUUUGUUUAUUCUAGUCCUGAAUAGUAUUUCAAAUUACAUUAUUACAUGGCAACUAUCUAUAGGGGUUUGAAUUUGCUUUAUCAGCUUGGAGGUACACAUACACAUCCCUGCCUUCUCCAGCAAGUGGAGUACUUGACAGCUGACCCUGUUUUUCUUCUCUUUAAUAAUUUGAUACAAAGGUUUUGGACCCUAUUCAUGAUUUGCAGAAAAGACGGCAGCUCUUCUGGGAUCCACCAUAAUCUGCUAUGGGGCAAGGGAAUGAAAGACCUUAACAGGUUCCCAGGCAGUAUCUGAGGUGUUGAUGAAACAGCAGGAACAUCUUGCCAGUGGUCACUUUUAUCUCCCACUGGUCUUUGCUGUUGCAUUUCUUAUGUGCUGCAGAGCCUGCUCAAGAGAAGGGCUCCACAUCUGAAUAGAGUUGAAGUGGAACAGCCACAGAAAUCAGAAAAAAAGAGAAAAAGAUACUAAAUGUCUGGUAGUCAUCCUCCACCAAGUCACUUAGUCAGGUUUAGCUGCCUAGUUAAUUAUCUCUGGCUGAAAGUUCUAGAAAAGUUUUGAAAUUUGGGGUUUGCUGCUUCAUCUUUUAAGAAGUACAUUGUUUGGGGGCCUUCAGUUAAGUAGUCCUGUCUUCAUGGAAACAGAAAAAGGAGUCUUGUGUUCCUCAGUACACAUCAGUAUGUGUGUGUAUUAUGUAGCUUUAGAGACUGUUUUAAGUAAUCCCUUGGCAUCUUGAUGGGCAAUCUGUGGUCUGAAUAAGUUUUUAAAUAUAGUUAUACUCCCAAGAAAGCGUUAAAUAAAAUAUACUUCCUUACUUGUGAAAGUAAUUACUCAUGGUAUUUGGGCUAUUUAUUAGGGCAAAAAAAAAAAUCAACAAAUGAUAAUGUAACUGAAUGCUUACCAAGUAAAUAAAGCCUUUCUGAAAUGAUUUAUAUUGCCACCGUAUAAAGAUAAAACACCAGGAAAUUGCCUCAUAUCUACUUAUAAGUUUAUUUUCAUACCUUCUAUAUGGUAAACCUCAAAUUAUUACCAUGGCCACAAAUAUUUAUUUCUCUAAAAGUGAAAUGGACUUGAUGAAAUAUUUGGAACUAUCAAACUGAAUUAAUCCUAAAUAAGAACAUUUAUUAUAGUUUAAUUCAUGGACAGUUCUAUUUGUCCAACUCUAACAUCCUACUUCCCUCCCUGCUUCAAAUUUCUCUACUUUCCAUCCUCUCCUUCUGAUGCUGUUCCUACCAUUUACCUGGCACCCUUAGUUUUCCAUUGACACUGAAGUCUUUGAUAGGGUGGAUGCUAACAAGGAAGGCACCAAAACUCCUCCAAGUCCCUUCUCCACCAUCCCGUGCUCUAGGAGGUCAAGAGGGAUGCGGAUAAGAUCUCUUACCCCACCCUGUUCUUUCUUGAAAAGGAGGAUGAGAAUAGCCAAGAGUGAGGGAGGCACUGUCAAGACCCUCCAAUGGUUUCUCCUCUUCUUCCCUCUCCUUAAACACCAAGGAGGAAAGUUGGUAAAAGCCCACGUGCUGCAGGAACAGGCACUGUACACUCAUCCUCUUCAGCAGGCCGCCAUCUUCGCACUGUUUCCUCACUCCUUUCAGCUGCCAUCCCCCGCUCCAUCCUUCUUUCCCAGUUGGUCUUGCCUUCCUCAUCCCUGGAUCUCCUCCCACCCCAGCUCUGCCUUUUUGCCCUCCUUCAUAGUGGAAGCCGAGGUCUGUGGUCCUAGGGAAGCUCAGACUUCCAGUUAUGGGAGGGAAGAUUUCCUUUUUCUACCUCCAGGGCUAAAUGGGUCAGGAGUAGUUGCUGUUAUCCUAAGUUGGAAUGCUAAAUUGAUUUUCCUGUAGAAACAUUGCCCACACAGGUUCUGUGUUUUGUUAUACUUCUGUAACCUUUUGGACAUUUAGGCUUUUGUGAGCGGGCUUGGAAACCUAGCAUAUUGAUCAUUGUCUCCUGGAAAGGCAAAGUCUGAGUUUCAAAUAGAUGAUUUUAAAAAUCAGCUUGUGCUCCAGAAAUUGUUGAGGGUUGCCUGCUUUUUGUUAAUUAUUCACUGAAAUGGUAGGUAUUAAUAGUACACCUUUAGCUGUCCAGAAUUAGAUUUAUGUGGAUCAGAUGGCUCUUGUGGGAGAUAAACUGAUAGGCUUUUUAGAUUGUCAAUGAAGAAUUUCUAAAUUUAGGCACAUGUUUUGAAAUAAAAUUUAAGUUAGUCCAUCUCAGCCUAAUAUUGUCAUUAAAGCGGACAGAUCUUGCAGUUUUGUUGAAAGAGCAUAGUUUUGGUUUUUCAUAAAAGGAAUAUCUUGUUCCCACCAUGAAUUACUGAUGAUUUGAAACUUUUCAAAGGUAUUGGACCUCUUGCAGUUAUUUUACCCUCAUUUAUUUAGUGUAAACAUGGGACAGUGUGUUUGUUUUACUUCAAGAUUUUAAAAUAAAGUGUUAGCGUGUUGAGGUUACAUACUGUUACCACUGUUUGUGAUGUUCAGACAAUUAAGUGAGGGAUAUGAAGGUAAUAAAAACAAAGCUAAGUACAUUUUAAAUUUGUUUUCCAUAAAUGUGUUCAGUCUUAUAUUGGUUGAAGGAAAUACUCCUAAUAAAAGGCAAGAUGGUUUUUUUUUUUUUUUGGUUUCCAAACCACUCUUUCGUUUGAAAAAUGACUUUCAGUAAGCACGCUGUGUUCAUUUUAAGAGUUUACCAAGUUAUUUAAUUACACAGCGAGUGCAGAGGUUAAAAAUAUGAUCUCGGGGUAAAAUGCCCAGAUGUUCAGAUCUGACACUAACUAGCUCUGUGUUCGUGGGCAAAUUACUUAAUCUCUGACCUGUUCCCUCAUUUUUGAAGGGAUAAUGUGGUACCUACCUCAUACAAGGAUUAAAUGAGCCAGAGGAUGUAUCAUAUUUAAAACAUGCCUAGCAAUGGUGAAUACUCAAAAAGAGUUAGUUCUUAUUAUUACGUUGUCGUCAUCAUUACUACUAUUAUUGUUAUUACUUUAGCUACUUUCGAAGAUGAUACGCCUUCUGUUCUGGGGUGUGGGCAUGAAAGAUAUAUUUGUUUACCUGGUAGCAAUUUUUUAAUGCAGAGUUUAUUUGAGAGGUUCAGGGAGAGAGCAGUAUGUUAACUGCUGGAUAUAUCCACAAUUGGCCAUAGUGCAGGAAAUUCAUAGAAUAUUAAGCUUAUUUUUUUCAGUAACACCAUUCCUUUUGUUAGGUAUAAAGAACUAUGCCUUUUUGAUGUUUGAGCAAAACUAGAUUAUUUGAGUAAUUGCAACGUCUUUAUUAAAAUACAGUUAUCUUGGUAUCUAAAGGCUAGAGUCUGUGCAGGGGGAGCCUCAAUUUCUAAAUGAUCCAUUGGUAAGACUUUUUUUUAAGCAGCACCAUUUUCCCACAGAAAAAUGUCACAUAAUAGUGUUCAGAUUCCCAAGCCAGCCCAACAUAUCUGAAUUUGAAUACUGAUAGUAUUAUAAAAACUAACUUUUAUGUGUAACAGUGUCUCAGCAGGAACAUGCACUGAGUACAUCAAGUACUGAAAGAUUAUGAACACAAUCUUGCAGAUAUGGCAGUAGGGCUAUCUUCCUUUGCAGUCCUAGCAAGGACCGUCAAGCCUUGGGAAGAGAACUCUCUCCUCUGGUAGAGGCCGAGGGACACUGUCUUCAGCCUUUUCUUCAAGUUUUUGACCGUGGAUUGUGUUGUGUCAAACUGGAUGAAUUAUCUUAGUUGAAUUUUCACCAGUUGAAAAAUUGGAGAUUUCUAGACUACUGAAAAGAAGUUGCUUUCAGAGCUGGAGAUGUGAAUAAAAUUUCUGUGCCAGGGUUGAUAAACCAUCUUGAGGAUUCCAUCCAGGAAACCCCAUCACAGUUGGUUGUUAUGUCUCCUUAGACUCCUCUUGGCUGUGACAGUUUCUCAGACUUUUGUUCUUGAGGAGUACUGAUCAGAAAAUGACUGUGGUGCUAGAAGAUCAUUACUUUUGGAAAGCCGGUUAACAUCCAUUUCCUAAGAGAAACUUGGCCACCAUUUGCUCUGGCAUGGCGCAAAGCAGCCCACAGCUUGAUAUUCAGGUUCUCCAUGAUCUUCGACAACGUUUCCCUGAAAUUCCAGAGGGCGUGGUGUCUCAGUGCAUGUUACAGAAUAACAACAAUCUUGAAGCCUGUUGCCGAGCCCUUUCCCAGGAGAGUAGCAAAUACUUAUAUAUGGAAUACCAUAGUCCAGAUGACAAUAGGAUGAAUAGAAAUCGCCUUUUACAUAUUAACCUGGGUAUCCAUUCUCCUAGUAGCUAUCACCCAGGAGAUGGAGCCCAACUUAAUGGUGGUCGAACACUGGUACAUAGCUCAAGUGAUGGACAUAUUGAUCCUCAGCAUGCAGCAGGUAAACAGCUGAUAUGUUUAGUUCAAGAACCACACUCAGCUCCAGCUGUUGUUGCUGCUACUCCCAACUACAAUCCAUUUUUUAUGAACGAACAGAACAGAAGUGCAGCUACUCCUCCUUCACAACCACCUCAACAGCCAUCUUCCAUGCAAACAGGAAUGAAUCCGUCUGCUAUGCAAGGGCCUUCACCACCACCGCCACCUCCUUCAUACAUGCACAUACCUCGGUAUAGUACAAAUCCAAUUACUGUUACAGUAUCCCAGAACCUCCCUUCUGGACAGACUGUACCAAGAGCUUUACAAAUUCUUCCACAAAUUCCAAGCAAUCUCUAUGGGUCUCCUGGUUCUAUUUAUAUUAGACAGACAUCUCAGAGUUCAUCAGGAAGACAAACUCCUCAGAGUACGCCGUGGCAGUCCUCACCACAGGGCCCAGUGCCUCACUAUAGCCAGCGUCCUUUACCUGUUUAUCCACACCAACAGAACUAUCAGCCUUCUCAGUAUUCUCCCAAACAGCAGCAGAUCCCUCAGUCUGCUUACCAUUCACCACCUCCUUCUCAAUGUCCUUCACCCUUCAGCUCUCCACAGCAUCAAGUGCAACCUUCCCAGUUGGGCCACAUCUUUAUGCCACCUAGUCCUUCAACUACUCCACCCCAUCCAUAUCAACAAGGACCUCCUAGCUAUCAGAAACAGGGAAGCCAUUCAGUAGCCUAUCUUCCAUACACAGCAUCUAGUUUAUCCAAAGGUUCCAUGAAGAAGAUAGAAAUUACAGUUGAACCUUCUCAAAGACCUGGGACAGCAAUUAAUAGGAGUCCUUCACCCAUCAGUAAUCAACCAUCUCCACGGAAUCAACACUCACUGUACACAGCCACCACGCCACCUUCAAGUUCUCCUUCAAGAGGGAUAUCUAGUCAACCAAAACCUCCAUUUAGUGUUAAUCCUGUGUAUAUUACAUAUACACAGCCAACUGGACCUUCUUGUACUCCAUCACCAUCUCCUCGAGUGAUACCAAACCCAACUACAGUUUUUAAAAUUACCGUAGGCCGAGCAACGACUGAAAAUCUUUUAAAUUUAGUGGACCAAGAAGAGCGCUCUGCAGCACCAGAACCUAUUCAGCCCAUUUCAGUGAUACCAGGCUCUGGGGGAGAAAAGGGAAGCCAUAAAUAUCAGAGAAGUUCUAGUUCUGGAUCAGAUGACUAUGCCUACACACAAGCCUUGCUGUUACAUCAACGAGCAAGGAUGGAGAGGUUAGCAAAGCAACUGAAACUUGAGAAAGAGGAGCUAGAGCGGUUGAAGUCUGAAGUUAAUGGUAUGGAGCAUGACCUGAUGCAGAGACGGCUCAGAAGAGUCAGCUGCACCACUGCGAUCCCUACGCCUGAGGAAAUGACAAGAUUGAGAAGCAUGAACAGACAACUCCAGAUAAAUGUUGACUGUACACUGAAAGAAGUUGACCUCCUUCAAUCUAGAGGAAACUUUGAUCCAAAAGCCAUGAAUAAUUUUUAUGACAACAUAGAACCUGGCCCAGUUGUACCACCCAAGCCAUCUAAAAAAGACUCCUCAGACCCCUGCACAAUUGAGAGAAAAGCCCGAAGAAUUAGCGUGACCUCCAAAGUACAGGCAGACAUCCAUGACACCCAGGCAGCAGCUGCAGAUGAGCAUCGAACUGGCUCCACACAAAGUCCUCGGACACAACCUCGAGAUGAAGACUACGAAGGGGCUCCAUGGAAUUGUGAUAGCUGCACCUUUCUUAACCACCCAGCACUAAAUCGCUGUGAGCAGUGCGAGAUGCCACGGUACACCUGAAUUCAGAAAAGUCUGCGCCAGGUUGAAAGUGAAACUUUGAGCACUACCAGAAGAAAAGGAAACCUCGGGACUCUAUUCAUCCACCCAGCCUUUUCAUUUUCGAUUGCACAGCGGGGAGGAGGAAUGGCUUUGUGGUCGUCGUUGUGCUCACGAAAGGAAAAAUGGGGAGGUCUUUUUUUUCUCCUUUCUUAACUCACUACAGAGUGAGAGAUAGAAAGGGAUACUUGAAACUGGGAAAGGAUUCACUCUGUGAAAGAAUGUACACACAGAAGUCAAGAGCUCUUCUGUGGUGGAAUCCCAAUUGUUAAAGUUACUGCUGAGUGGCCCUUAUUUUUUAAAGUAGUACUUUGAAUCAUAGUAUGAAAUGCUACAGUUUAUGCAAACUGUGAAUUCCCAGAGCAGACUUACCUGGUCACCGCUCUCUGGAAAACCAAGGCUCCCCGUGCUUCUUCCCAUUGCUUCCUACUAAAGAGGACAACAGGAAAAAGCACCUAGAAUAUUUGGGGGGGGGGGGCAAAUUAAUUAAGGGUAUUUGUAAUUGCUGCUUUUUUCAGGGGUAAUUUCCAACACACAUACAUGCACACAAACAAAAUGUUUUAAAAUGUGAUUUGUAGCAGUCAGGAACUAGGCAUAUCAUGCCUUUGUUUAAAAGUACAAUCAGAGGUGGUAAGAUGCCUUUGGCUUGUACAGUGUGAUUCAUCGAGCUCUAUCAACACUGGUAACUAAGACCUACUUAUGCCACAUAAGAGAUGCAUUUUUUUAAGUUACUGCAUGUUUUUAUUAAGGCCAUUGGUUUUCAAAAUAACAAGUCCUUACAAAGUAUGAUUUUAUAAAUGAUAUUCUCGUAAAACUGCGCUUUGCCAGUAGCACAGUGAAUGUAUGCCAAAUGCAAGUCCAUUCCAAAAUCCAUUUGGAAAUCUUGAGCUCAGCUGUGGUUCUUAAACUUUUGCAGUCCAUAGGGCCUUUUUUUUUUCCUUCCAAUUUUGUGAUAAAUUCAUGAUGUUUACAGCACAGAUAAAACUUUGUGCCAUAAUCCUAAUUUAGCUGAAAUCAAUAUUAACUGUUCAAUAAAAACUUACUUGCAUAUGUUAACAAACCAGUGUGAGGGGAAUUACAGUUGGCCAACGACAAAGUUGCACACUGCAUUAUUUAGGAAAGGAGGGAUUGUCAAAAAUUAUUAAGAGAAAGGUGAAUAUAGAGGACUUUGAAACAACUUUUAAAAUUUAACAUAACUGUAUCUAGAGGUCAAUUGAGUCUCUACAGGCAGUUCAGAUCAUUUUAAAGCACUCCUUAUUUAUGAAAUAGAACUUCAGGGUGCGGAUAAGAGAUAUAAAGUCAUGUGACUCACUAGGGUGCAUCGCUGGAAACUUAAUAGCACAUUUCAUUAAGGUCUCUGCCAUUGUUGGAGUUCCUUCUUAGCUCAGAAUUGGAGUUUUGGAAUCUUCCCCUCAUUUUGGUGAGUAUAAACAGCAAUAAAGUUAGUAGGUUCUCCCAUCCUAAAGGAUUUUACCUGAGGAUAUCGUCUUAGGAAUAUCCAUAGACGCUCCCAUCAGGUUUCUCCCCCAACCCCCCUACACCGCCCCCCCACUUCUAAUUUAGCAGUAAUCUCUGGCAGACCUGGAAAAACAAGCUGCUCUUAAUAGCAUAAUGAAACCAAAGGCGUAAUAACUCAUCAUAGUUUUCCAUCAGAAUCAUUUCACACUCUGCCUACAGCUUUGAAAACAUUUUUUCAUAUGUGAAAAACUCCCCAAAAUAUAUCCACUAGUCUCCCAAAGGAAGCAUGGUAAUUAACACUGAUAAAAACAUCUCUCACACAACAACUGUGGCAAAACUGUGAAAAUAACGGUGAGAAAGCAGAUGGGCUUAAAAGCAUGGUCCCCAAAACAACGUUCUUCAAAGGUUUUUGUAACACUGGUCUCUGUCUCCAAUAACAGUCUAGCCGUCCUACUGUUCUGUAAUAUGCCUUUGCCUUUGUAUGGUUUCAUAUCUCUUUAGUGAUGGUCAACCCCACUUGGUUUUAAGUUACAAUUUAGGGGAAAUAUAUAUAUAUAUACUGCUUGGUGUCCUAGCUAAAAGGUUUACCAGUAUUCAUAGUGAUAUGCUGAAGUGGAGGCAAUUAACUUGGCAGUUGUCAGUUGAGAAUGAAAGUAGCAUGUCUGAAAACAGUCUGAUGCUUUAUAAAACCAUGUAGAUGACUUUAAAACUAUUGCAUGAAAAUACAUCAAGGUUAAUAAGCUGUUAUACAGUAGAUGCAUGGUUUCAAUCCUUUGGUGAUAUUAUCUAGUCAAUCAUUGUUUUCACCUGCCAGGAAAAGAGAGAAAACAGUCUAUUGGAUAGGUGUAAAGGGUGGGGUAUGCGGUAUCAGAUUGAUUUUAAGGAAGUUUUGUACAUGUUAAUUUUUAAUUGUGCACAAGUUUCAUAUGCCAACAUAGGCUGUAUUCAGUUUUAAAAUAGGCAAAAUGACUUGACACUGAUAAAUCUGGUAUGUUUAACUGUGUCCCAUAUGUAGACUGCUUUUUGCCUAUGACCAGUUUGAACAAGAAUUCACCCAACUUUCAAGAUGCCUUUUCAAAAGGAUCUUGUAGUCAGUUGGUAUGUACAGACAAUUGGCAUGGAAGUGGUAGGAUAUAAAUCGGAUGACGCCUGGCUGCUGAGGUGCCAGCUGGAUCAGCUGGUGCACUUCUUGUUUCUUGUAAGAGGUUUCUUUAAAAUGACUAGUUUGAUGUAUCUGGUAACAUAUAGGCCUGACUAUACAUUUUACAUUAUUUCGCUAUUUUGUAAACUGGGAUUUUAGAAAGCACGUUUGCCAUUUUGUUAAAGUACAUUGCCCCUUAAAUUUUGGAGUAGUUUUUAAAAGUUUAAAAUGGUAAUAGAGGAGCCAGAAACUUUUUAAGCAUUGUAAAAUGUUUUGAAUUGAUAUUGACUUUGUUUGGAAGAGAGUAGAGGCAGGGGGCUUUAAAGAAACAAAGAAAUGCAUUGUAAAAAUGUAGUUUUAGAGCAAAUUAAUAAUGAUGGUGGGGAAAGUGUUGCUAAUUUGUUUAUUUCCCUGGAAGAAAUGGGAAGUGUGAUAAGCAGUUUAAUUUUUAAGGAGCUGGUCUCAAUUUUAGUACUUUUUAAUUAUGCAAAUAAAUCAAUGUUUCCUUAAAUUUUGUCAUUGCUUUGUCACAGUUGUCUAGGGUUCAUAUCCAACCUUCUGUGGCAAUUCAAUUUUAUAUAGUCUUUUAAGAGGUAAUUGUAAUGUAUUUCUGACAGUAUAAACAAAAAGAAUAUAAGGCAUAGAAGAAUUGUCCUCUAAAAAUAUCAAUGAUGUAUCCUGGAAUGUGAAGAUGUCCCUUUAUAGUUAAAAAUUGAAUUAUUUUAAUAUUGUACCAUUGUUAGACCUUGAAUGAGUCCAUGUUACCGUGUGUGUCUGUAUAUCUAUCUGUAGAGAAAGAAAAAUGACAACUGAAAUGUUACUUUUAAAAAUCAGAAUAAAUUGGGCACUGUCUGUGUUGCACCACUACUGUAUCUUUUCGAAAGAAUUAACAGUAUUUGCCUAUUGUAAAGGUUAAUUCUGAUGACGUUUUCACAUUCACCAGACUUUUUUUCCUGUAUUAUUUGCAUCCCCAAAUAUUUAAUACAAGUAGAUUCUGCAUGGCUUGGGCAUUCAGAGAUUAAUAGAAUGAUGACUCAAUUUUAAUUCUAAAGCCAUGAAAAGUUACUUUGAGACUGAACAAUUCUGAAUUAUUUAUGAUACCCAAUGUCCAUGUUUCUUUCCCUACUGUAAAAGAAUUGAUCAGUUUCUUCAUUAAAGCAGCAAAAACUUAUUAAAUCUUGUAAAUACCAUGUCUCUUUUAGAUUUCUGUGUAUGCUGUGAAUGAAAUCAUUUUGAGAUGAAAUUGUACAAAGGCAUUUUAAAAGGCUCUGCAUGCAUCGUACCUCCAAACAGUACAUAUUCGGAAAGUCAAAGAUUCCUGCAAAAUAAAUAAACUAAAAGCAAACACUA